AGGCUCCCGGGGCUGAGUCUAAAUCACUCAUCAUUGGUUAAAGCCGAGCUCACAGCAGAAUAAGCCACCAUGAGGCUGUCGGUGUGUCUCCUGCUGCUCACGCUGGCCCUUUGCUGCUACCGGGCAAAUGCAGUGGUCUGCCAAGCUCUUGGUUCUGAAAUCACAGGCUUCUUAUUAGCUGGAAAACCUGUGUUCAAGUUCCAACUUGCCAAAUUUAAGGCACCUCUGGAAGCUGUUGCAGCCAAGAUGGAAGUGAAGAAAUGCGUGGAUACGAUGGCCUAUGAGAAAAGAGUGCUAAUUACAAAAACAUUGGGAAAAAUAGCAGAGAAAUGUGAUCGCUGAGAUGUAAAAAGUUUUUAAUGCUAGUUUCCACCAUCUUUCAAUGAUACCCUGAUCUUCACUGCAGAAUGUAAAGGUUUCAACGUCUUGCUCUAAUAAAUCACUUGCCCUGAA